CUCUCGCGCAGGGCCCCCGCGGCCGGGGCAGUCCCGCAGCCGAGCGCAGCCGGGCGCGCGCCACCGCCCACUCGCCCUGUGCCCGCCGCAGCCCGAAACUGGCCACGGCCGGGAGCGGAGGGGACAGCGGGGAUCGUGAGCUCCGGCCCGGGCGAGCGGGUGCGUCUGCCGCAGAGUCGGCACCUGAAGGACAUGGAGGAAAGACCGGCAGAGACCAAUGCCAAUGUGGACAACUCGGCGUCCCCCUCGGUGGCCCAGCUGGCCGGGCGGUUUAGGGAGCAGGCGGCUGCAGCCAAGGAGACACCAGCCAGUAAACCAACCCGAAGGAAACCGCCCUGUUCCCUCCCCCUGUUCCCCCCCAAGGUAGACCUGGGCCAGAAUGGUGAGGAGAAAUCACCACCCAAUGCGAGCCACCCUCCUAAAUUCAAGGUCAAGAGCUCGCCUCUGAUUGAGAAGCUUCAGGCCAAUUUAACCUUUGACCCAGCUGCUCUACUGCCUGGGGCCUCACCCAAGAGUCCUGGACUCAAGGCUAUGGUGUCGCCAUUUCACAGCCCACCUUCUACCCCCAGCAGCCCUGGUGUGCGAUCUAGGCCCAGCGAGGCAGAGGAGGUGCCUGUCAGCUUCGACCAGCCCCCUGAAGGCAGUCAUCUGCCCUGUUACAACAAGGUGCGGACGAGGGGCUCAAUAAAAAGGCGCCCUCCCUCCAGGCGAUUCCGAAGGUCACAGUCAGACUGUGGAGAACUUGGAGAUUUCAGGGCGGUGGAGUCAUCUCAGCAGAACGGUGCUAAGGAAGAGGAUGGGGAUGAAGUGUUGCCAUCCAAGAGCAAGGCCCCAGGAUCCCCUUUGUCCAGUGAGGGAGCAGCGGGAGAGGGAGUGAGAACCCUGGGACCUGCUGAAAAGCCUCCUCUGAGGAGGUCACCCAGCAGGACAGAGAAGCAGGAGGAGGACAGGGCCACAGAGGAAGCCAAGAACGGUGAAAAGGCCAGGCGGAGUUCAGAGGAGGUGGACGGCCAGCACCCGGCCCAAGAGGAGGUCCCGGAAUCGCCCCAGACCUCUGGCCCAGAGGCAGAAAAUAGGUGUGGGAGCCCCAGGGAGGAAAAGCCAGCUGGAGAGGAAGCAGAGAUGGAAAAGGCUACAGAGGUGAAGGGGGAGAGGGUGCAAAAUGAAGAGGUGGGACCUGAACAUGACAGCCAAGAAACAAAGAAGCUGGAGGAGGGAGCUGCAGUGAAGGAGACCCCCCACAGUCCCCCUGGAGGAGUGAAGGGCGGAGAUGUCCCCAAGCAGGAAAAAGGCAAGGAAAAACAACAGGAGGGGGCAGUGCUCGAGCCAGGCUGCAGCCCCCAGACCGGCCCUGCCCAGCUGGAGACCAGCAGUGAGGUCCAGAGCGAGCCAGCAGUCCCCAAGCCGGAGGAUGACACUCCUGUCCAGGACACUAAAAUGUGAAGAACAGCUCAUUGUGCCCCAGUGAUGAAGUUGCUGGACACAUCUCUUUGCAGGUAGCAGCAACAGUUGUAGCAGCAGCAGACGAAGCCAUUGCAGAGGCAGAAUAUGCUGAGUGUCUGGAGUCAGCCUGAAGACACAGGGUGGAUUAUUUCCUGGCCUCCACACCAAACGUUCCCUUGCAGAUGGAGACUGAAUCUGAGGGCAGCAGACUUUUAUCAGCUUGAGUUUAUGUCAUUUGAUGGACUUGGUUCAACAACAAGAACUUACUUAAAACAAUGUACUGUGGUGAUGAGUCCCAGGGGCACUGGUCAGCCUGUGGAGCCCUGGAUGCUAUCCACACCCACCUAUCCCUGCAGCUAAUUUAGCUGAUCUCUAAUUUAACUGAGCUCUAAUUUAGCUGAUCAGAUUUUGCUUGGGUAAAGUUCCUUUUUAAUGUUCUAAAGUGUUUACGGUUCUCAAAUAUCAGUUAAAAACUAAUUUUAGGUGGCCAUAAACAUAAAAUAGAAACCCUGUAAGUUACAGAAGACCCUAAAUUGUAUCAAAACCCUAGAGACAACUUUUCAAUUUGAUCCAAAUUUGAACUGGCCAACCAGUCUUUAAAACACUGGACUAGAAGAGAUAAUGAUUGAAACAUUUAAAAAAAAAAAGUGCUCCAUUCGCAGGAGCUUUUCCUGUCCUGUGGUUUUCCAGUUGGUGACCACCAUGGGAGGUCGCUGGCUCGGCUCACUCCCUUCUCCCACCCUUGAGAAUGUGGAGAACUCCCAUGGAGAGGCAGAAUGGCAGGAGGUUUCAUGUCCCGCGUUGCAUCUCCUCCUGAAAGAAAAGCAGUGAUACCUGAAUAAUGCUGGCUCUCCGAUUGAUCCUGUGAGGAUGAAUUUGCAUUUCCAGAAUCCUUGAGCAUGGAUUAGAUGUUUCCUGGGAGGUGCCUUGAGUACCAUUAUGUGCAAGCUACAUAAUUAAAACAUUUUUCUUAGUUUCCCUGGGAAGCUUUUCUUGACUCACAGCCCAGGUUCUUCUGCCCAACACAAAAGGAGUGAGUUGGGGUCUUUAGUCUCUUCUUAUUGGGUAGCUCUUGCUUUAAUAUUCUGUUUGGUGAGUGUAAGGGAUUCUGCAAGGGACAGGGGGCCUGACUACCCAGUCUUUGACUUGUAUCCUCUCCCCUCUUCAUACACUCCUGCUGAAAAAUGUUAAUCCAAAUACACAUUUAAACUUAGGGUCGGUCCUUAUUCUGAUUUGAGUAUUUUAAUGUCUCAGUGUGCUGAUUUGGUAGUUGGAAGAAUUAUUCUUCUGGAGGUCUGUUAGACUACAUCCUACACUGACUUCAGAAAACAGUCUGUCAGACAAAAAGGCCUUAUGUCACCACUGGUACCUCAGUUUCCUCAUCCCAUUUACAGUUUUUCUAACUCCAGGGUAGUGUUUAGUGUUAAUAUUUGGGAUAUAUUUUUUUUCAAAACUGUUUUUAAGUAGUUUGUAAUUUGUAACAAACUUGUAACCUGGUUGGGACUGAUAUUGUCAUAGCUAUGAUAAACUUUGGAUAUUAGCAGAAUUUGGGAGAUGUGUGUGUCAAUUAUUUUGAGAUCUAUAAACUUGUCUGUCUAUCUAUCUAGCUGGCUAGCUUGCUAUCAAUCUAGCUACCAUCCAUUUAUUGACAGAGAAGUCUACCCCUAAACAAUACUUGGUUUUAUUUAUAUAUGUCUUUGGGUUGUUUAUACACAUGCACUAUCUGGGCAAGUACUUUGUGAAUAUGUGCAUGAUUGUGAAUGUGUGAUGAAAAGGGCCACUUUACUUGAGGAAGGCAUGGAACAGAAAGUAUGGGGUUUAGAUAUGAAAAAUGAAACUGCAUUUUUCUUCUGGAGGGUCUAAACAUAGUAGCAGACGAGAGAGGGGCAGUAAAAAUGACAAGAAUGUGACAUUGCGGCACCAUGCUUGUGGGCAUCAGAAUACCUUUCUAUCCCCCAAGUCUCCUGUUAGUCACAUUAUUUGGUGUAUUUUGUGAAAAAAAUAGAGGCCCCAUUCCCAGGGCUUGUUCAUUAAUAAAGGGGGCUCUUGGCAGGGAACUCAUGAAGUACAGGGACUGAUUUUUGUUGGUGCUGCAGCCCCACUGCUUAAAACUCUCCUUUCUCAAAGCAACCAUGAUCAGGUGUUUUAUUUGCAUGGUUGAUACUGGAACUUCUAAAUUUGGGAUUAAAGAAAUUCAUCUGUGUCUUAGGUAGCACAAAGUUAUUAACAGGCCAGGAAGACCUUGUUUCUUUCAGGCUUCCAUAAUGGGUUUGAAAGAAAACACGGAUUCUUCUACAGCAACAGAGUUAAAGAAAUAGUCAUAGUCAUUCUUCCACGAUCUUUGUAGUCUAGCUUGAAUUUCAAACUGUGUCCUUCCUUACUCCAGAGAGGGAGCAAGAAAAAAAACCUGGAUGCUUUGAAGGGAUCUGCCACUAUUUAAAAGGGGAUUAGGAUUCUGUUUCAGCUGCAUGUGGAACUAGGUAAGCUUCAGUGGCCUCAGAACUCCAGGCCCCUCACGGAGAUCACCCUGAACAAUGCCCAGUUUUUCAUGCAGGUUUUGUCCUAUGACCAGUUAACUACAUGUUCAAUAAAUAAAUGUCAAAGAAAUAAAUGCGUGAAAAGGCAACCAGUUCAUCAUCUUAUGAUUAGGUUUUCUUGAUUAGGGAUGUGUUUAGUACAGCUGAAUGAACAAGUUCACCCAGCUGCUGGUGACAGAAACCCAACUCAAACUAGCUGAUGAAAAACAGAACUAUACAGAUCAAUGAAUCUCUCCCCCUUUUUCAGCCUCAUAGAACUGAAAAAAACAAACCUAAAUACAGUCACCCAAGUGAUGUCAGGAAUCUCUCAUGGUAUUGGUCUCUGCUUUCCCUCGUAUUGGCCAUAUUCUUUUUUUUUUCUUUUUUAAAAACUUAUUUAAUUAGUUUUCCUUAAUAGUUGCAGCCAAGGCUGUCUCUUUUUUCUCUUCUUUUCUCUUCUUUUUUUUUGAAUGAGACAGAGUCUCGCGCUGUCACUCAGGCUGGAGUGCAGUGGCACAAUCACAGUUCACUGCAACCUCUGCCUCCUGCAUUCAAGCGAUUCUCGUGCCUCAGCCUCCCAAGUACUGCAGUUACUUUUGCACCAACCUAAUAGCUCGGAUUACAAGUAUGCACCACCAUGCCCAGCUAAUUUUUGUAUUUUUUAGUAGAGACCAGGUUUCACUAUGUUGGCCAGGCUGGUCUCAAACUCCUGGCCUCUAGUGAUCUGCCUGCCUCGGUCUCCCAAAGUGGGAUUACAGGCAUGAACCACCACGUCCAGCCAGUCAUUUUCUUAAGUAGGUUCUUCCCAGCCUGCAAACCCAGUGAAAGGGCUUAUUCUUUCACCAUUACUGUGGGGAAAAAGUCCUGUAGAGGCUUUCCAUAGGCCCUGUGUGACUCACGUGUCUAUACCUGAAUCAACUGUUACAACCAAGCAGAUGCAGAGACUGCGUGCCCUCUCCUGGAGCUAGGAGCUAGGUGAGUCAAUCCUGCACUUUCUCUACAAGGCUUGCAAAGGUGAGCAAGAAGAUUCCCCAAAGUGAAAUCAGGGUGCUGUUACCAAAAGAAGCUAUGCUGGCAGGCAAAAAACAACAGCUGUUUCCCAUAGGGCAAAACCUGAAACACCCAAUUACUAUCCCAUUGUUUGCUUCAAAAUUAAAUUUUGUUUGACCCCAACUAGUUCUAGUCAAGUUUUUGCUCGAUGGACCACGUGAAAAAAGGAUAAACAAUGUCUCUAUAUAAUGCAUGAUCAGGUGGUUUAUGAAGAUGUCAAGAGCACUGAACAAAAUCCAAAUGCUCACAUAAAAUGGGAUUAGGUUUCAUAAGCCACCCAAGAAAAUCAGUCUCAUUAUUUUAUGUAAUAAUGUAUUACUGUGCCCAGAGCUAACCUGUAGCUCUAGGGGAGUACAAUGUGUUUGUAUUAUUCUUCAUUGUACACAGUGCCUCAGACAUAGUAGGUAUUCAAUAAAUAUUUGUUAAAUCAUGAA